GUAAAGGGUCUUCUGAGCUGCAGUGGCAAUUAGACCAGAAGAUCCCCGCUCCUGUCUCUAAAGAGGGGAAAGGGCAAGGAUGGUGGAGGCUUUCUGUGCUACCUGGAAGCUGACCAACAGUCAGAACUUUGAUGAGUACAUGAAGGCUCUAGGCGUGGGCUUUGCCACUAGGCAGGUGGGAAAUGUGACCAAACCAACGGUAAUUAUCAGUCAAGAAGGAGACAAAGUGGUCAUCAGGACUCUCAGCACAUUCAAGAACACGGAGAUUAGUUUCCAGCUGGGAGAAGAGUUUGAUGAAACCACUGCAGAUGAUAGAAACUGUAAGGUGAGAAACUGCUUCUUCUUCAGAGUGGGGAUGGGGAGAGGGGAAUAAAGAUAAAGAUUUCCAAUGCAUGUUUUUUUUAAGAUGUUGGAAAGUGUAGAAUAUUUUCAGUAUUUCAAUCCAAGGAGAAAUACACCAAAGUUAGUUUAAUGUGCAUAUGUUAUAUUUUGAACAAUGGGUACUUGCUAUAGCAUAAAUCUCAGUUGUAUUUGUCUCUUACCAUAUACUGUUCACAUUUUAUAUCAAACUUGUAUUUCAGAAAAUAUUUAAUAAGGUUUGUUUGAAAGAGAGAUUGCAUUUUGUUUAAUUCCCCAGGUUGCCUCAGAUUGACUAAAUAGACAGUUUGCCUCAUUCUAAGGCUUUCUUUAGAGGGACGACUAGCUGCAAAGCACUGGUUUAGGAUUUUUGUUUUUAAUAUAUUAAAUUUUUGUAUUUAGAUGUAUACUUUUUAAUCAAAUUAUGAAUUCAAAUUUACAUAAUAGAAAAUCUAGAAGUAAUAGAAAUAACAAUAGGAUAAUUAACUGAUCAUGAUUUAUUCAAUUAUACAACUCUUUCAAAAAUCACAUCGUCUUCCGUAUCAGAAAUCUGAAUUGUAUUUAUUGCUAUGUUCUGCAUUUUGUUGUUGGUCUCAGUCUGUUGUUAGCCUGGAUGGAGACAAACUUGUUCACAUACAGAAAUGGGAUGGCAAAGAAACAAAUUUUGUAAGAGAAAUUAAGGAUGGCAAAAUGGUUAUGGUAAGUAAUGACAAUUCUCCAUUCUUCCUUGUUUUUUUCUCCUCUCCGCACACCUCUCACCUCCUUCCUUCUUCUUCCCUCCUCCUUCCAUUCUUCCUCCUUCCUUCCUUCUUUAAUAAUACAUCACUGGCAAGGUUCUUUAACUAUAUGUAAAACAGGGGAAACAAAAAGAUCCCAGUUAAUUUUCUUCUUCAGCUCAACUUCUUUGAUUGUAGAAAAAGAGAAAAAUUCAUGUGUAGUUAAAAAAAUAAAAGUUGCCAUUGAUUUGCCUAAAACUGUGUCAAAAGAUUUUUUGUAGGAUAACUAUGGAUGUCUCUCAAAUAAAAUUUAAUAUAAAGCCCAUAAUCACUGAAAUAUAUAAAGAUAAUUGCUAUUAUAAGAGAAUCUCAGACAGAUGACUUUAUAGCUCCUGUAAUAAGAGAUCUUUAAACAGUUUAUAUUUUAAUUUAUAAAGUUACACAAGUUCUGGGCAGAUAAUUUAGAAUAUAACAGAAAAGUAUAACAAAAAAAUUAAAAUCCCCUCUGAUUUCUCAUCAGUGAUAACCCUUUUUUUUUUUUUUUUUUGAGAUAAAGUCUUGCUGUGUCACCCAGACUGGAGUGCAGGGGGUGCAUUCUUGGCUCACUGCAACCUCUGCUUCAUGGGCUCAAGCGAUUCUACAACCUCAGCCUCCUAAGUAGCUGGGACCACAGGUGCAAGCCACCAACGCCGGGCUAAUUUUUUUGUAUUUUUGUAGAGAUGGGAUUUCGCCAUGUUGCCCAGGCUGGCCUACAGCUCUUGAGCUCAAAGUGAUGCUCCCGCCUGCUGCCUCGGCCUCCCAGAGUGCUGGGAUUACAGGCCUGAGCCAAGGCUCCCAGCCCCCAAAGAGAACCAUUUUGAUGUUACUUCUUUCCAGUUUUUUUCUCGAAUGCAUAAUAUGCCUUUUAAACAUAUAUAUUCAAUACUAGGUAGACAUGAAAAAUAUUUUUUUCAAUCAGCCUCUUCUUACUUACUAGGAAUUAUCUGUAAAAGAGGAUUUAUUAGUGUCCUAAGGCUGCCACAACAAAGUACCACAAACUUGGUGGCUUAAAACAACAGAAAUGAAUUUUCUCAGUUCUGAAAGCUGGACGCCUGAGAUCAAGGCGACCCUAGUGUUGCCAUCCUUCUGCGGGCCCCCUCCCUUGCUUCUUCCUACUUCCCGGAUGGCUCCUGGCAAUCAUUGAGGUUGUUGGGCUUACAGUUGUUAUUACUCUGAUCCAUUUCUGACUCCAUCUUUACAAGACUUUUUCCUCUGUUUUUGUCCUAAAUUGAUCAAAUAUAAAAUAAUUAACAAAUAAUUUAUCUAAUGAUGGAGUAGUAUCACAAACUAGGAGAAAUAUUAUGCCUUCACCAAGCCUUCCUCAGACACUUUUUGUGUGACCUGCAAUGGUAUAUUGAUGAUACUGACAUAGGUGGGUAGGCUCAUUCAAUUUUGGAGGAGGGUGUGAGAAUGCUUUACAUAGUCCUUGUACGAUGACAGCAGAGAAAGUUUUGUUGUUUAAGAAUGGGGACUCAUGUUUCCUUCUCCCCUUGACUACUGCAAUCAGCACUGUUCUGCAUUGAGAUAUUCAUGUUUCUGUGGAGAUGGAGGUGGGGAGCAGAGGGACAGUUUUCCUUUCAUGUUAAAGGAUAUUUGCUCACAUUUUUUUGGCAACAAUCAAUAAAAGAAAGGACUCAUUUCUAAAAGAUUCGCUCUGAAGUUCUCCUUUAUGCUUUUACCUCCAUUUUUUCCCAGAACACAGAAAAGUAGAUAGCUCAACCGUGGCAUGCAUGACUAUGAUCAGGCAAGAUUGAGUUCAAAAAGGAAGACUAAAGCAAUAGACUACAAGGAUAUACUAUACUCCUGAACAUCACAUCAAUACAUGAAAACCAUGAGCACCAAAACCCCCUAAGUUCUGUAAAGUGGUUUUAUAAUAACUCUUCAAGUUAGAUUUGACAUUAGAGUAAUAGAGCUGAUGUUCCGCAUCCUAUCCACCUACCUACCUGCGUUCACAUAGGCUAAACCAUGACAACCAAAACAAGGAGAAUAUUUGUACCUUUACAUGUUCCUCUUGAUUUUGGAACAAGUCAUUCCAAAUACCAUCAGCUCAAAUGACUGGAUUUUCUAAUGGCUAUUCAAAAUUUAUCUAGGUUAAGAAUUGAAAACUGUUAUGUAAACCUAUUAUAAAACUCAUUCACUUUUAAAGCAGAUAGUUGAGAAAACAACGUAGACACUCCAUUUCUCACACCUGAUCUGCUCAAUUACCCUGAUAAUUUAAGGCUAAAGAAAUUCUUUUGACUUGAAUCUAAAGUGCUAAUCCCAGUGUUUGCUUCAUUCUCAUUUCAGAGACAUAAACUGUAUAUCAAUAUAGGGUCUCUUUUCAAGAUGUGAAAUGCUUAUGCAGCAUUUAAUGUUUGUAAAUGUCAUUCUUUUGCAUAAUACUUAGAUCACAUAUAUGAUGAUCUUUAAAAUUCGGUGACUGAAGUUCCUGUAUAAAAAGAUUUGAUUAUCUUUUGAACCUUGCAGACCCUUACUUUUGGUGAUGUGGUUGCUGUUCGCCACUAUGAGAAGGCAUAAAAAUGUUCCUGGUCGGGGCUUGGAAGAGCUCUUCAGUUUUUCUGUUUCCUCAAGUCUCAGUGCUAUCCUAUUACAACAUGGCUGAUCAUUAAUUAGAAGGUUAUCCUUGGUGUGGAGGUGGAAAAUGGUGAUUUAAAAACUUGUUACUCCAAGCAACUUGCCCAAUUUUAAUCUGAAAAUUUAUCAUGUUUUAUAAUUUGAAUUAAAGUUUUGUCCCCCCCCCCCUUUUUUUUAUAAACAAGUGAAUACAUUUUAUAAUUUCUUUUGGAAUGUAAAUCAAAUUUGAAUAAAAAUCUUACACGUGAAA